AGAGAGCAAACUGCGCCUGGGCAACCAGUCGGGAGGGUGAGUCCCGCGCGCGACAGAAGCUUCUGGCGCGAAUGGAGAACCAAGAGUUUCUAAGUUCAUCUGCGCCGUCCGAGGUGACCGAUGGGCAGGUCUCAACAGAAAUAUCCACUUGCUCCGAAGUCUUCCAGAAGCCCAUUGUGCUCAGGAUUCUCGACACUCACAGAGAGCUUGAGGAGUCCGAGGAUCCCGAGAAACACGAGAAUCCCGAGGAACCCGAGGAGGUCAGGGAGCAAGACCAGAGAGACGAGUCCGAGGAAUGUGAUGAGCCUCAUGAGUCCUAUGAGCCCCACGCUCCCUAUGCGCCCCACAAGCCCCGGGACUCCUAUGCACCUUACGAACUCCAUGGGCCCCAUGCAGCCCCCAAACUCCUCAAGGCCCGUGAACCCCGCCAGCUCCGCCACACCCGUGAGCCCCGCAAGUCCCGCGAGGCCAAGGAAACCGAGUUGCUUCCCAGCGCCGCAGUAAUGAUCUCCCCCUCUCUGAUCACCAGAGCCCCGCCACGGCCUCAGCUGUCUUUCCUGGGUGCAAAUCCUGUUUCCUGUGACUUUGUAAGGAAAUGUUUUUCUUCUAGGAAGAGAACCCCAAAUCUUUCAAAGCCUAAAAAGCAAUGGGGAACUCCAGACAGAAAACUGUUUUGGGGAAAUCAAGAUCCUAUUCGCCCUGUUUCCCAGGGUGCUUUGAAGGCUCAGCUGACCAAAAGACUUGAGAACCUUGCCCAGCCCAAGGAAGUUUCCUGCCACUAUGUACCUAACAGGGCUCAAUACUACCACAGCUGUGGAAGAGAGUCUGUAAUUUGGGAGAUCACUCCUCCUGCAUUGUUUAGACAACCCUCCAAAAGGAUCCAGAGGCUGUCACAGCCCAAUGGAUUCAAAAGACAGUGUCUACUAAAUAGACCCUUCAGUGAUAACUCAGCAAGAGAUUCUCUUCGAAUCUCUGAUCCUUCUCCCCGGAUAUUACAACUCUCAGUAGCCAAAGGCACAGACCCAAACUAUCAUCCUUCAAAAAAAAUGCAAACCAAGAUUUCACUUUCUACCCUGAGUGCGAUUGCAACUCCAAGAAUUAUAGAGCUUGCCCACCCAAGGAUCAAGUUAGAGGGUCUGUGCUAUGAAAGACAAAGAAGUGAACUGCCCAUCCGUCCUGUACCUCCUGCUGCCAUGAUAGCUAAACCUAGCCCCCGAACAAUAGCUCUAGCGAAGUCCAAGUCUGUUCAUCAAGAUUAUCUACCUGACCGUGAUGCCCAUUGGCCAGUAUCUUAUGCUACUACUCAUUCCAAAGCAUCACCUAGGAUUCAGGAACUAGCUAAUCCAAAUAAGAGAGGGGUAAUACCACAUAGCAGUUUUGAACUUGAGUUUUGGAAUCAGAUAGAACCUGAAGUUGUCUCUGUCAUGGAUUAUUUACCAGCCAUGUGAAGAUGCAGCAAGAAGGUGCCAUCUUGGAAGGAGCAAGCAGCCAUCAAUUGACAUUGAAUCUUCCAGUGUCUUGAUUUUGAACUUCCCAGGCUGUAGAACUGUGAGAAAUGAAUUUCUAUCAUUUGUGAAUUAUUCAGUUCAUUGUAUUUUGUUAGAGCAACCUGAAUAGGCUGAGAGAGAUAGUGAGAGUCAAACAAAUGGAAACACAUCCCAUGCUUAUGGAUGGGUAGAGUGAAUAUUGUGAAAAUGACCAUACUGCCAAAAGAAAUCUACAGAUUUAAUGCAAUUCCCAUUAAAAUACCACCAUCAUUCUUCACAGAAUUAGAAAAACAAUCCUAAAGCUCAUAUGGAACCAAAAAAGAGCCUGCAUACCCAAAGCAGGACUAAGCAAAAAGAGCAAAUCUGGAGGUAUCACAUUAUCUGAUUUCAAACUACUAAAAGGCCAUAGUCACCAAACAGCAUAGUACUGCUAUAAAAAUAGGCACAUAGUCCAAUGGAACAGAUAGAGAACCCAGAAAUAAACCCAAAUACUUACAGCCAACUGAUACUUGGCAAAGCAAACAAAAACACAAAGUGGGGAAAGGACACCCUAUUCAACAAGUGGUCCUGGGAUAAUUGGCAAGCCACAUGUAGAAGAAUGAAACUGGAUCCUCAUCUCUCACCUUAUACAAAAAUCAACUCAAGAUGGAUCAAGGACUUAAAUCUAAGACCUGACACUAUAAAAAUUAUAGAAGGUAACAUCAGAAAAACCCUUCUAGACAUUGGCUUAGGCAAGGAUUUCAUGACCAAGAACCCAGAAGCAAAGCAAAUGCAACAAAAACAAAGAUAAAUAGCUGGGACUUAAUUAAACUAAAGAGCUUCUGUACAGCAAAAAGAACAGUCAGCAGAGUAAACAGACAACCCACAGAGUGGGAGAAAAUCUUCACAAUCUAUACAUCUGACAAAGGACUAAUAUCCAGAAUCUACAAUGAACUCAAAUCAGUAAGAAAAAAAAAUCCCAUUAAAAGGUGGGCUAAGGAUAUGAGUAGACAAUUCUCAAAGGAAGAUAUACAAAUGGCCAAGAAACAUAUGAAAAAAAUGCUCGACAUCACUAAUGAUGAGGGAAAUGCAAAUCAAAACCACAAUGCGAUACCACCUUACUCCUGAAAGGAUGGCCAUAAUAAGAAAAUAACAAAUGUUUGUGUGGAUGCAGUGAAAAGGGAAAGGGAACACUUCUACAUUGCUCAUGGGAAUGCAAACUAGCAUAACCCCUGUGGAAAACAGUGUGGAGAUCCCUUAGAAAACUAAAAGUAGAACUAUCAUUUGAUCCAGCAAUCCCACUACUGGUUAUCUACCCAGAGGAAAAGAAGUCAUUAUACGAAAAAGAUACUUGCACACACAUAUUUAUAGCAGCACAAUUCGCAAUUUCAAAAAUGUGGAACCAACCCAAAUGCCCAUCAAUCAAUGAGUGGAUAAAGAAACUGGUAUAUGUAUAUGAUGGAUUAAUACUCAGCCAUAAAAAGGGAUGAAUUAAUGGCAUUUGCAGCAACCUGAAUGAGACUGGAGACUAUUAUUCUAAGAAGUAACUGAGGAAUGGAGUGUAUGUUCUCAUAGGUGGGAGAUAAGCUAUGAGGAUGCAAAGGCAUAAGAAUGAUACAGUGGACUUUGGGAACUUGGGGGGAAAGUGUGGGAAGCGGGUGAGGGAUAAAAGACUACAAAUCAGGUUCAGUGUAUACUGCUCGGGAGAUGGGUGCACCAAAAUCUCACAAAUCACCACUAAAGUACUUACUCAUGUAACCAAAUACCACCUGUUCCCCAAUAACCUAUGGAAUUAAAACAUUUUUUAAAAAAGGAAAAAGAGUCAGAAUACACAAAUGAACAAAAGCCAGGCCACAUAUGGCAACAGAACUCUGCCUCACAACCUCUGCAGCAACUAUGCCAGGAAGCUAAACCACAGCCUCUGCAACAAUCAUGCCAGAAUGGUCAGAAUUUGCUCAAUGGUGCUUUAUUGGUGCCUAUGUUUUUGCCCCCACUUCUAACUCAGGACCAACCAGAGAAAGCCAAAUACGCUCCCUAAGCCAAUCACGUAAGACCCCCUAGUUCUAGUUAACCCCCUUCAACUUCCCCACACAAGCAGCCUCCAAUCAGAGCAUAUCCAAAGCCUCCCCACACCCCUGCUGCUGUAAAGCUUCCCCUCUCCCCUAACUGCCUUUAAGUUUCUGUCAAAUGCAAGUGUCUCCCUUGCUUUAGCCAGCUCUAAAUAAGUAGCCUGUGCGUGCUCCCAUUUGGGUGGUCUUUGUUUAUUUUCACAACAAUGAGCC